AGAACCUGAGCUCCUUGCUAAGCUGCAACCUUCCUCUGCUAGCACCAUGGCCACCCAGACCUGCACCCCUACCUUCUCCACUGGGUCUAUCAAGGGCCUCUGUGGCACAGCAGGCGGCAUCUCUCGGGUGUCCUCCAUCCGUUCUGUGGGCUCCUGCAGGGUCCCCAGUCUCGCCGGUGCUGCAGGGUACAUCUCUUCUGCUAGGUCGGGCCUCUCUGGCCUUGGGAGCUGCUUGCCUGGCUCCUACCUGUCUUCUGAGUGCCACACCUCUGGCUUUGUGGGGAGCGGGGGCUGGUUCUGCGAGGGCUCCUUCAACGGCAGCGAGAAGGAGACUAUGCAGUUCCUGAACGACCGCCUGGCCAACUACCUGGAGAAGGUGCGUCAGCUGGAGCGGGAGAACGCGGAGCUGGAGAGCCGCAUCCAGGAGUGGUACGAGUUUCAGAUCCCAUACAUCUGCCCAGACUACCAGUCCUACUUCAAGACCAUCGAAGAUUUCCAGCAGAAGAUCCUGCUGACUAAGUCUGAGAAUGCCAGGCUGGUCCUGCAGAUUGAUAAUGCCAAGCUGGCUGCUGACGACUUCCGGACCAAGUAUGAGACAGAGCUGUCUCUGCGGCAGCUAGUGGAGGCCGACAUCAACGGCCUGCGUAGGAUCCUGGAUGAGCUGACCCUGUGCAAGGCUGACCUGGAGGCUCAGGUGGAGUCCCUGAAGGAGGAGCUGAUGUGCCUCAAGAAGAAUCACGAGGAGGAAGUCAGUGUACUCCGUUGCCAACUUGGGGACCGACUGAAUGUGGAGGUGGACGCUGCUCCCCCAGUGGAUCUCAACAAGAUCCUGGAGGAUAUGAGAUGCCAGUACGAGGCCCUGGUGGAGAAUAACCGCAGAGAUGUGGAGGCCUGGUUCAACACCCAGACUGAGGAGCUGAACCAGCAGGUGGUGUCCAGCUCGGAGCAGCUGCAGUGCUGCCAGACGGAGAUCAUCGAGCUGAGACGUACGGUCAACGCGCUAGAGAUUGAGCUGCAGGCUCAGCACAGCAUGCGGAAUUCCUUGGAAUCCACCCUGGCCGAAACCGAGGCCCGCUACAGCUCCCAGCUGGCCCAGAUGCAGUGCCUGAUCAGCAACGUGGAGGCCCAGCUGUCUGAGAUCCGCUGCGACCUGGAGCGGCAGAACCAGGAGUACCAGGUGUUACUGGACGUCAAGGCCCGGCUGGAGGGCGAGAUCGCUACCUACCGCCACCUGCUGGAGGGAGAGGACUGCAAGCUUCCUCCCCAACCUUGUGCCACGGCAUGCAAGCCUGUUAUUAGAGUUCCUUCUGUCCCCCCGGUGCCCUGUGUCCCCUCUGUGCCCUGCACCCCGGCUCCCCAGGUUGGCACUCAGAUCCGCACCAUCACCGAGGAGAUCAGAGAUGGGAAAGUCAUCUCCUCCAGGGAGCACGUGCAGUCCCGCCCGCUGUGACAGCCCACUUGGUCCACCAGGGCAGGGCCCUGACCACAGGAAGGAGGACACCCCUGUGGCUCCUGGAGGCUUAACGACCCUGCCCUUCUCUAGAGGGGUCCCCCUACGCUUAGCAGGUUUUUCUACCAAAACACUCCCCGUAUUGUGUUUCCGGACUUAACUGUGCUUUUACGCCAUGCAAAACCAGGUUUCCUGGAAAUUUACCCAAUAAAGUGUGUUCUCCUGGCAUAGCAAACUCAA